CAGGUGAUCUGCCCCUGUCUCAGCCCCCCAAAGUGCUGGGAUUACAGGCGCCCGGCCUACAUGUUUAUUGUUUAAAAACCGGGAAAGUAUAGAGAAGAAAGUAAAGGCUCCCCACCCCUAGAGAUAACCGCUGAAAGUAUUUGGUCUGUUUCCUGCCCGGCUUUUUCCUACACACACUUUUUGGCGCCUUAAGUCGGGCUCCCCCCGGACAGGAGGGGCCCCUCCCAGGCGCUGGUGUCUGCGCCCGCCCCCCGCAGCCUUGUCCCUGCUCCGGGGGGUCCCUGGGUCUCUGGGGCAUAUCGUUGCUUCACUGCUCGCUCGAGCCUCCAGGGAUCGGGCCGCCGGGGCAGCGCAGAGAGGCGGGGACAGGCGACAGCGGCGCAGAGUGGCUCCUCCCGGGGCCGGCCCAAGCGGGGGUCUCGGUGCCUGCGAAGCGGCAGGGGUCGCUCGGGGCCCAGUGCCCUCUACGUCCCGUCCGGGUCCCAGCUGGGGCGGGGCGCGCCCAGUGUUUCCGGGAGGAGCGGCCCGGGCGCGCGGCAGGUGCGGCGGCGCAACUCGCGGGUCUUCUCCACUGGCCCCUGAGAUUGCCAUCACCUCCAGCUCCUCCUCUCCUGAAGUUGGCAGCCCCUCCUGGGUUCCAGCCUCCUGAGAUGCCAGACCCACUGGGGCAGUACCCACAGGCCCUGAGCCUACAUCAACCACCCCAGUGACACCCCAAGCCUGCAGCAUUUUCCACCCCCAGCCCCCUGGUCCCACCUUGCCUUCCGCCCACCUUCCCACCUGCUGCAGGGAGGGCCCUCGGCUGAGCCUUCAGACACACUUGCACCCCAUCCGCUCCCCUCCUGAAUUUCUUCUGACCCUCCCUUGGCUUCACAGCACCUGAAGGCCAGGCUGAGGCCCCCUGCUCUCAUGGCCAGCCCUGGAAAGCCUGGGGCUGAUGAGGCCCAGGAGGAGGAGGGGGAACUCGAGGGGGGCUCUGCAGGGCCGCGGGCUGCAAUACUGGAGCAGGCUGAGGAGCUGUUUCUGCUGUGUGACAAGGAGGCUAAGGGCUUCAUCACCAAGCACGACCUGCAGGGUCUCCAGAGCGACCUGCCCCUCACGCCAGAGCAGCUGGAGGCUGUGUUUGAAAGUCUGGACCGGGCUCACACUGGCUUCCUCACCGCCAGGGAGUUCUGCCUGGGCCUGGGUGAGCCUGUGGCCUGCCUAUCCCCCACUGCCCAGAGCUGGAGGCCUGAUCAGGAGGCCUGGCACUUGUGGCGCCCUGAGGGCUGCCGGUGCCUCUCGUCCUCCUCCCUCCAGGGCCCGUGCUUUGUCUGCACGCACUCGCGCCUGGGGGCUCCUAGCUGCGGUGGAGUGUGUGGAGCUGACCUUCCUGGCCCCCAGCUCCUCUCCUGUGCUAAGCUCCGGGAUGUUUGUGGGGGUGGCGUCAGCCCAGGGAGCGAACCCCUGCAGGACUCCCGAGGAGACCUUUGAGUCGGGCGGGCUCGACGUGCAGGGCACGGCGGGCUCUCUGGAUGAGGAGGAGGAAGAGGAGGAGCGAUUCCACACUGUGCUGGAGCAGCUGGGGGUGGCCCCGGUCCUGGGCAAUUCCCGCCCGCCCUCCAGGCAGCGGGCUGUGAGGACGCUCUGGGCCAGGCUGCAGCGCGAGCGCCCCGAGCUGCUGGGCUCUUUCGAGGAUGUUCUGAUACGCGCGUCGGCCUGCCUGGAGGAGGCGGCCCGGGAGCGCGACGGCCUGGAGCAGGCGCUGCGGAGGCGCGAGAGCGAGCACGAGAGGGAGGUGCGCGCUCUGUACGAGGAGACGGAGCAGCUUCGGGAGCAGAGCCGGCGCCCGCCGAGUCAGGUGGGCCUCGGGCCCCGCCCCUCCCGCCAGGCCCAAUCCCACCUCGCUGGCCUCCCUGGCUCCGCCUUCUCUGAAUUAAUCCCUCCCCGACGGCCCCACCUCCGCGGGUCCAGGCUGCCCUCAGCCCGAGGAGAUCCCACUGGGCCUCACGUAUCACCCCCGUCCGGUCUUCUCCACCCGACCCCGCUCCGCCCGGGCCCACUCCCAGCCCCUGGCCCUCCGUGUACCUCUUUUGCAUGGCCGAGCGGCCGGCGGAGGCUCAGUGGUCCUCCGUGCGUCCCAGAACUUCGCCCGCGGGGAGCGGAGAAGCCGUCUGGAGCUGGAGCUGCAGAGCCGCGAGCAGGACCUGGAACGCGCGGGCCUGCGGCAGCGGGAGUUAGAGCAGCAGCUGCACGCCCAGGCUGCGGAGCACCUGGAGGCACAGGCCCAGAACUCCCAGCUGUGGCGGGCGCACGAGGCGCUGCGAACGCAGCUGGAGGGGGCGCAGGAGCAGAUCCGCAGGCUGGAGAGCGAAGCACGAGGCCGCCAGGAGCAAACCCAACGGUGCCGUGGGACGGGGCUGGGCGGGCCCCGGUGCGUGUCCCGGGGGCGGGGCCGACGGGCGCUCAGGUCUGGGCCACUUUCAUCCCCAUCUCAAGUCCCAGGCCCGCCCCGUGGGAAGGAGGAUCUUCUAGGGGGUCCGGGGGCUCCCCAAGGAGCCUUCCUGCAGCCGGGUCACCACCUCCCAUCCACAGAGACGUGGUCGCCGUCUCCAGGAACAUGCAGAAAGAGAAAGUCAGCCUGCUACGGCAACUGGAGCUGCUCAGGGAGCUGAAUACACGGCUGCGGGAUGACAGGGACGCCUGCGAGGCCAGGCGGGCGGGCAGCAGCUGCAGGAAGGCUCUGACAACAGCCCGCCUGCCUGGGCCCACCUGCUGCUGCUGCUGUUGCUGGGCUCGGCCCCCCAGACGCGGCUCUGGCCACCUUCCCAGUGCCCGGUGACCAGCCCCGAGUGACUCACGGACCAUGAGCUAGAAGCUGCCCUUGCAGGAGGCUUGUCAUGGGUCGGGGGUGCCCACUCAGGAUGCAGGCUCUCCCCAGUGGGCCCCAGGCUCGCCUGACUGAAGACAUGAAGGACCUAGCCUAGGAGUGGUCAGGGUCCCGGGAGUGGCCAGGGUCCCGUGUGUGCCCUCUGCCAGUCUUCGCUCUGUCCCCGUUCAAUCAACCCCAUCUCAGUUCAGCAGAAAACCCCCUCGUCAAAUAAAACCCACUGACUGCACUGCG